GUUGAUAUCAAUAUGGCGGUUGUCAGCCAGACAAAGACAGUCAGUCUGAUGUGAUUGAGACAAGGGAGGUUUUUCAGGGGGAGACUGGGAGAUAGGGGCCUCCCCUCCCCCUUCUCCUCUUCCUGCGCCGGCCUCAACCCCUCCCCAGUCCCCUCCCGACGGGCGCCCCACGCGGAAGACACCCCUCCCCCUCCCGCCUUCCCUCCUCCCUAUCUCAGCCCUUCGUACUGGGACGUUGGGGAGGGGGCUGUGCCGGGCGGAGAGAACUCAGCGAGGAUUCUGAGGUGAGUCGAGCGGUUUUGAAGCCGGACUACCUCAAGUCUCUUUCCUCACUUCUUUCUCUUCACUUAAAACAAUUUUUUUGGAGGGGUUUUGGGGAGGAAGUGAGCGGACGCUGGGGAUGGGUCUCGUAAGCGGCCGGAUUGAGAGGAGGGAGGAAGCAGGGGGCUUCCGAGUGGGUGACCCAGACGCGGGCUGUGGGGUGGGGCAGUUCGUGGGGUCCGGUCCUGGAAAGGCGUCGACUGCCCCCCAACUCUUCUGGUUUCCUCUACGAUGAGCGGAAGGUUUGAAUCCUGGAGGUGGGGUCUCCGGUGUGGAGUUCUGGAAACUGUGAGGUGAUUUGCAGGUGUGUUGGUUUGUUUGGGGUGUGUAAGUGUGUUUAAACUGUGUGACGUGUACUUGUGUGCUCUGCUCGUCUUGGAGCGGUGUCUGUAGAUGGGAAGUUAGACAGCGCGAGUCCUCGCUCGCUCUGGGCCUGGGCUGAGGGGCGGGCGUGAGGUCCUGGUGCUGGGCGUUUGGGCUGGCGACGUGGUGCGAGGCGGCCGGGCUCAACAACUCGCUUGUGUCCCGUCGCCCGCUCACACUCUGCCACUCGCCUCCGCCCCCUCCCCUGGACGAAUCUCCACCCCAAACUCCAGCCACGAGAACUGUAGAGAUGGUGUGAUGUGGAGAUGGAUUUUUUGCAUCCUCAAGUCGGUAGAUAGGUGGGAAAGGAAAAGUGUUUCUUAAUAUUUUAUUCCGGAACCGUGUUUUGGUUACACUAUUGGGGCUACUUUGAAAGGCGUCCUCCACCCACCUUCACCCCGAAACAGUAGGUAGAGGUAUCUUGUCUUCGUGUGAAUUAGAUGAAUAAUUGCUGAAGAUUCGGGGGGCCUGGGGUGGGGGUCGGGAGUGCUGGAUUGUGUACGCGUCUGUGUGUGUCUACUAAGGAGACGGAAUGUCUGUUAUGUAUCUGGAGAUAGGGCGACUUAUUUUCGUAGCAGGAGGAACUGUUGGAAAUUAUUUGCGGGAGAGGGGGUGCGCCGAAAGGCGCUGCUUGUAUUUUUCUUCUACUCCACCCUGUUCUGUCUUGCAUUUGCCUGAAAGCUGGUGGAAUGGAACAGUGAAGAAGCAUUGGAAUGGUAGAUAACGCAGAUCAUCUCUGGAAAGGAUAUUGAUCCGCCUCAUGUAAAGUAUGCUUAGUUCCUUUCCAGUGGUUUUGCUGGAAACCAUGUCUCAUUAUACAGAUGAACCCAGAUUUACCAUAGAGCAGAUAGAUCUGCUUCAGCGACUUCGGCGUACUGGAAUGACUAAACAUGAAAUUCUCCAUGCCUUGGAAACUUUGGACCGUCUUGAUCAAGAGCAUAGUGACAAGUUUGGAAGAAGGUCCAGCUAUGGAGGAAGUUCAUAUGGGAAUAGUACUAACAAUGUCCCAGCAUCUUCCUCUACAGCUACAGCUUCCACACAGACGCAGCAUUCGGGAAUGUCCCCGUCACCUAGCAACAGUUAUGAUACUUCCCCACAGCCUUGCACUACCAAUCAAAAUGGGAGGGAGAAUAAUGAGCGAUUAUCUACAUCCAAUGGAAAGAUGUCACCAACUCGCUACCAUGCAAACAGCAUGGGUCAGAGGUCAUACAGUUUUGAAGCCUCAGAAGAGGACCUAGAUGUAGAUGAUAAAGUGGAAGAAUUAAUGAGGAGGGACAGCAGUGUGAUAAAAGAGGAAAUCAAAGCCUUUCUUGCCAAUCGGAGGAUUUCCCAAGCAGUUGUUGCACAGGUAACAGGUAUCAGUCAGAGCCGGAUCUCUCAUUGGCUGUUGCAGCAGGGAUCAGACCUGAGUGAACAGAAGAAAAGAGCAUUUUACCGAUGGUAUCAACUUGAGAAGACAAACCCUGGCGCUACACUAAGUAUGAGACCAGCCCCCAUUCCAAUAGAGGACCCUGAAUGGAGACAAACGCCUCCCCCAGUCUCUGCCACAUCUGGUACUUUCCGACUGCGACGAGGGAGUCGAUUUACCUGGAGAAAGGAGUGCCUGGCUGUUAUGGAAAGUUACUUCAAUGAGAAUCAAUACCCAGAUGAAGCAAAGAGGGAAGAAAUUGCAAACGCUUGCAAUGCAGUUAUACAGAAGCCAGGCAAAAAGCUGUCAGAUCUGGAAAGAGUUACCUCCCUGAAAGUAUAUAAUUGGUUUGCUAACAGAAGGAAGGAGAUCAAGAGGAGAGCCAAUAUUGAAGCAGCAAUCCUGGAGAGUCAUGGGAUAGAUGUGCAGAGUCCAGGAGGCCACUCAAACAGUGAUGAUGUCGACGGGAAUGACUACUCUGAGCAGGAUACUUGGCAAGUACGCAAUGGGGAGGAGGAGGAGGGAAGAAGUUCAGAGGGAGGCAGAGAAGCAGAGAAGGAUGACAGUACGAGCCAUAGUGACCACCAAGACCCCAUCUCAUUAGCUGUGGAAAUGGCAGCAGUCAACCACACUAUCUUGGCAUUGGCCCGACAAGGAGCCAACGAAAUCAAGACAGAGGCCCUGGAUGAUGACUGAUCAGGGAGGUUAAACAUGACAAGUUAACUUAGUUUAGACGUAGCACCUUAGCAGACUUUCCUCGGUCCUUAACAUGUGUUCUUACAGUAUAACUUGCAGUUUCUUGUAUGUCAGGUAGCUGUUAGGGUCUUGUUCUGUGAAGAUGGCAUGGUGCCCUCAGCCUUUGCAUAUACUCUCUCAGUAUUAACUCCCAGUAAAUAAUAACCAACCAACCAACCAAACUUCCCUCUCCCAGCCCCCGAGGCUAGAAAAUCUUGCUGCUCCGUCUUAGCAUUCCAAGAAAGUGCUUCCAGGUAUUUAGAUAGCCCUCAGUUCUCAAAUAUUAGACUACGUGUAAAAUCUUGGGUACCUUUAGAUUCUUGUAACACUAGUCUGUACUCCCUUUUCCUUCCCCAAGACUGAUAGGAUGCAAGCUGAGGUCGUGGCACAGGAAUGACAGACACCAUUUGGGGAGUAUCCACAGAGUCAAAGGAACACUAGAAUCCCCACCUCAGCGUGAGGAUAAUUGAUUUCCAGCUGCAAUAAGCCGUGCCUCAUUAUAGCCACACUGUGGCUAGAUUAUACUUCUUUGGGUGCUGUGCUAAGAAUGUCAAUGGAAAAAGCCGAUCUCAGAUUUUGUUUGAAGUUAACAUGCCUGACACAGACAUCCUUUCCUCUCACAAGCUGUGUGACUUAGUAGAUAAAAUACUGCCUUCUGCCUUUGGGACCAUGAUUAAAAACAAAGACAAAAACCAAAAGUCAUUAAAAAAAAAAAAAAAAAAAACCCAGCUUGAGAGCAUUGGAAAAAAAAAAUAUGAGCUGAAUGUCUAAUGGAUGCUAAGUCCAGUUUUCAGAACCACUGUACAUUCCACGGCACAGUUAGCAGUGCCUGCCUGGAAAAGUUUUGGAGGUCAUCGUGGAAGUUGCUUUGCCUCCUGUCAGUGUCCCCUUUCCCUGCUACCAAAAAAGUCUUUCAAGGAUGGAGCUAAGGUCAAAAAUGAGUGAAAAAACUUGCAGUGUUUGUAUCCAUUAAACGGAAGCCCCCUCACUCUGAGAGGUCACUAGAGGACUUCAUAGUGGGGUUGUGCUGCUUAUCACAGAUGCAGACACUUGCCCAGAUAGGAGCAGAGAAAAGCAGGGGACGUUUCCUACUCACAUUGUGGCUGUAUGAGAACACGAUGGGACUGCUUUGCUGUUCUCUUUACUCUGUCCUUGGAGAGGUGUGAAAAGCUGUAUUGCUACAGGCAAUUUAUUUAAUAAUUGGAAGCCAUAUUGAUAAUGGAUGUGGUAAUAUUUGUAAAGUUUAAUCUACUUUAAGCGGCAGUAACUAAUGGAAUUUUUUUCCUUGAUCACAUAUGUAGCACUUUUGUUACUUUUUAAAGAUAUUUAUAUUUGAUAAAUCUUUUUUUCAUUUUGAGAACUCAAAAUACCAAACAGUGAACUUGCAUUCUAAAGUCACCCUGUGAUCACCUUGUCAUCUAGUAGCAAAAUGAUGAACUAUUCAUGCAUCAAAGAAAAUUACAUCUGCUGGCCUUGUAUGAAAAUGAUCUCUUGGCAUCCCGAUUAAAUGACACACUGUCACUGUGGGUAAGAGGAAAGAGCCUUCAAUGUAGCAGCACAGGGUGCGCCUGAAAGAGGCACAACUGCUGUGGAUUUUCUGCCUCGCUCCAUCUCUCCUAUGUAUAAUGAAGCCUUGUUUAAAGGGGCAUGUGGGGCUGGAUGUUAAGCACGGCUUCUUUUUGUCCGUUACCUGAAAACAAUUUCUAAGAUAAAAGGAAGGUGCCAUUUCCUUACCUCUUCACCCAUCCUCCUCCACCAAAUGUAUUCAACUUAAAACUGUGAGAGAGAGAGACUGAAUGACCUUCCUCAGUUUUCCCUUUCUCAUUCAGGAGAUACUGAAUAUCCGCCAGUUUGUAGUUGGUUUCCUUCCACUUAAGGCACACGCUGACUGCAUCAUUUCCUUAUCUGUUAAUCCUGCUUAUGUGAGUGUGAGGAAAGUCUUUGAGAGGGCAUGAAAGUGCCACCUUAUAUAUGUCUGUGACUUUAAAGAGCUAUAUGCAGGGCCUGGUCCCACUUUUGUCCAUGGAUUUCAGGGGGAAAAAAUAUAUGUACUUUUUUCAGCUUCCAAGCAUUGAA